GUCCUCCCUAGGGCCUAGCGGGACGCGGCUGCGGUCAGAGGAGCAGGAGGAGGUCCCCCGACAUGCCUGAGGCAAAACCAGCGGCCAAAAAGGCCCCCAAAGGCAAAGAUGCCCCCAAAGGAGCCCCCAAGGAGGCUCCCCCUAAGGAGGCUCCUGCAGAGGCCCCCAAAGAAGCCCCACCCGAGGACCAGUCCCCGACUGCAGAGGAGCCCACCGGCGUUUUCCUGAAGAAGCCGGACUCCGUCUCAGUGGAGACUGGGAAGGACGCAGUGGUCGUGGCCAAGGUGAACGGGAAGGAGCUCCCAGACAAACCGACCAUCAAGUGGUUCAAGGGGAAGUGGCUGGAGCUGGGCAGCAAGAGUGGCGCCCGCUUCUCCUUCAAGGAGUCCCACAACUCCGCCAGCAAUGUGUACACCGUGGAGCUGCACAUUGGGAAGGUGGUACUGGGGGACCGUGGGUAUUACCGCCUCGAGGUCAAAGCCAAGGACACCUGUGACAGCUGUGGCUUCAACAUCGAUGUGGAGGCACCCCGUCAGGAUGCCUCUGGGCAGAGUCUAGAAAGCUUCAAGCGUACGAGUGAAAAGAAGUCGGAUACUGCAGGUGAGCUGGAUUUCAGUGGCCUGUUGAAGAAGAGGGAGGUGGUGGAGGAGGAGAAGAAGAAGAAAAAGAAAGAUGACGAUGACCUAGGCAUCCCCCCGGAGAUUUGGGAGCUCCUGAAAGGGGCAAAGAAGAGCGAGUACGAGAAAAUCGCCUUCCAGUAUGGCAUCACCGACCUCCGGGGCAUGCUGAAGCGGCUGAAAAAGGCUAAGGUCGAGGUCAAGAAGAGUGCAGCAUUCACAAAGAAGCUGGAUCCAGCCUACCAAGUGGACAGAGGCAACAAGAUCAAGUUGAUGGUAGAGAUCAGCGACCCAGACCUGACCCUCAAGUGGUUCAAGAACGGCCAGGAGAUCAAACCAAGCAGCAAGUACGUGUUUGAGAACGUUGGUAAGAAGCGAAUUCUUACCAUCAACAAGUGCACGCUGGCGGAUGACGCUGCCUAUGAAGUAGCUGUCAAGGAUGAGAAGUGUUUCACCGAGCUCUUCGUCAAAGAACCUCCAGUCCUAAUUGUCACACCUCUUGAGGACCAGCAGGUGUUUGUGGGUGACCGGGUGGAAAUGGCAGUGGAGGUGUCAGAAGAGGGUGCCCAGGUGAUGUGGAUGAAAGAUGGUGUGGAACUGACUCGGGAGGAUUCCUUCAAGGCCCGGUACCGCUUCAAGAAGGACGGGAAGCGCCACAUCCUCAUCUUCUCAGACGUGGUCCAGGAGGACAGGGGUCGCUAUCAGGUCAUAACCAAUGGCGGCCAGUGUGAGGCCGAGCUGAUUGUGGAAGAGAAACAGCUGGAGGUCCUGCAGGACAUCGCGGAUCUGACGGUGAAGGCCUCAGAACAAGCUGUGUUCAAGUGCGAGGUGUCUGAUGAGAAAGUGACGGGCAAGUGGUAUAAGAAUGGGGUCGAGGUGCGGCCCAGCAAGAGGAUCACCAUUUCCCAUGUAGGCAGGUUCCACAAGCUGGUGAUCGAUGACGUCCGCCCCGAGGAUGAGGGAGACUACACGUUUGUGCCUGACGGCUACGCCCUGUCGCUCUCGGCCAAGCUCAACUUCCUGGAAAUCAAGGUGGAGUACGUUCCCAAGCAAGAGCCACCAAAGAUCCACUUGGAUUGCUCGGGGAAGACCUCAGAGAAUGCGAUUGUGGUUGUGGCUGGAAACAAGCUGAGGCUUGACGUGUCCAUCACAGGGGAGCCCCCUCCCGUCGCUACCUGGCUGAAGGGAGAUGAGGUAUUCACGACCACCGAGGGCAGGACCCGCAUCGAGAAGCGGGUGGACUGCAGCAGCUUUGUGAUUGAGAGUGCGCAGCGGGAAGACGAGGGCCGCUACACCAUCAAGGUCACCAACCCCGUCGGCGAGGACGUGGCUUCCAUCUUCCUGCAAGUUGUAGAUGUCCCAGACCCCCCGGAGGCUGUGCGCAUCACCUCGGUUGGAGAGGAUUGGGCCAUCCUUGUCUGGGAGCCACCAAUGUACGAUGGGGGGAAGCCAGUCACCGGGUACCUCGUAGAGCGGAAGAAGAAGGGCUCUCAGCGCUGGAUGAAGCUGAACUUUGAGGUCUUCACAGAGACCACCUAUGAGUCCACCAAGAUGAUCGAGGGCAUCCUCUAUGAGAUGCGUGUCUUCGCCGUCAAUGCUAUAGGGGUCUCCCAGCCCAGCAUGAACACCAAGCCUUUUAUGCCUAUUGCACCCACGAGUGAACCCCUGCACCUGAUAGUGGAGGAUGUGACAGACACCACCACCACACUCAAGUGGAGGCCUCCGAACAGGAUCGGGGCAGGUGGCAUCGAUGGGUACCUGGUGGAGUACUGCCUGGAAGGCUCCGAGGAAUGGGUCCCUGCCAACACCGAGCCCGUGGAGCGCUGUGGCUUCACCGUCAAGAAUCUCCCGACCGGAGCCAGAAUCCUCUUCCGAGUAGUUGGGGUCAACAUCGCGGGGCGCAGCGAGCCGGCCACCCUGGCCCAGCCGGUCACCAUCAGGGAGAUUGCGGAGCCACCCAAGAUCCGGCUUCCCCGCCAUCUCCGCCAGACCUACAUCCGCAAAGUGGGCGAGCAGCUCAACCUUGUCGUCCCCUUCCAGGGAAAGCCCCGGCCCCAGGUGGUGUGGACCAAGGGCGGGGCCCCGCUGGACACCUCCCGCGUGCACGUGCGGACCAGCGACUUCGACACCGUGUUCUUCGUGCGCCAGGCGGCCCGCUCCGACUCCGGGGAGUACGAGCUGAGCGUGCAGAUCGAGAACAUGAAGGACACCGCCACCAUCCGCAUCCGCGUUGUGGAAAAGGCUGGGCCCCCCAUAAACGUGAUGGUGAAGGAGGUGUGGGGCACGAACGCGCUGGUGGAGUGGCAGGCCCCCAAAGAUGAUGGGAACAGUGAGAUCAUGGGGUAUUUCGUCCAGAAAGCAGACAAAAAAACCAUGGAGUGGUUCAACGUCUAUGAACGUAACAGGCACACUAGCUGUACUGUGUCCGACCUUAUCGUGGGCAAUGAAUACUAUUUCCGAGUUUACACCGAGAACAUCUGUGGGCUCAGUGACUCACCUGGUGUCUCCAAGAACACGGCCCGCAUCCUCAAGACAGGAAUCACCUUCAAACCGUUCGAGUAUAAGGAGCAUGACUUCCGGAUGGCUCCCAAGUUCCUGACACCUCUCAUAGACCGCGUGGUCGUGGCUGGGUACUCGGCAGCCCUCAACUGUGCUGUCAGAGGCCACCCGAAGCCGAAGGUGGUCUGGAUGAAGAACAAGAUGGAAAUCCGUGAAGAUCCCAAGUUCCUGAUAACCAAUUACCAAGGAGUCCUGACGCUGAACAUCCGUCGCCCCUCGCCCUUCGACGCUGGGACUUACACCUGCCGGGCCGUCAACGAGCUGGGCGAGGCGCUGGCUGAGUGCAAGCUGGAGGUCCGAGUGCCGCAGUGAGACCUGUCCCCUACCUGCCAAGACAAUUGGUGGUGGAGUCCUGACCCCAAUCCCCAACCUCCCAGGACUGUGUUCUUUCUGGAGUUUUCGCUGAGAACAAAACAGUGUUGUCUGGA